GUACAACAGCAUGAGCUCCAAGCUUCAAACGCAUUCUCAUGCUCAGACGAGCACUUUAUUUUUCAUCAAGUUAUUUUUUGCAUUGUUUUGGAGUAGCUUCGAAUAAUAAACACAUAUUUCUGCUUUAAAUUUUUAAUAGUUAACUACAUUCAUGGGACAACCAAAGCAAGAAAGCCUCAUGUUUUGGGGGAAAGUUUGAUAUCAGCAAUGUCCAGACAAGGCUUGCUAUGGACUGAAUUGUGUCACCCCAAAAUUCAUGUGUUGAAGCUUUAACCCCUAUUACGGCUUUAUCAGGAGAUAGAGGCGUUCAUAGCUAAUCCAACUUAAAUGAGGUCAUAGGAUGGGUCCAUAAUCCAAUAGGACUAUGGUCUCUUAAGAAAAGGAAGAGAAAGAUCUCCCUCUGCCCACCAUAUGAGGACACAGAAGGGAGGCAGCCAUCUGCAAGUCAAGAAGAGAAGCCUCACCAGAAUCCAACCACGCUGGCACCCAGAUCUCAGACUUCCAGACUCCAGAACUGUGAGAAAAUACAUUUCUGUUGUUUAUGCCACCCAGUCUAUGGUAUUUUGUUAUGGCAGCCCAAGCAAGACUCUACUAGAAAAUUCUUCUUACAGAUGAUAGAGUGCAAAUCUUAAAUAACAUUCAAAUAAUAAAUUAAUAAAAGGGUAAGAUAGUGAAUGGAACCAUAAAAUAUGAGUUGGACUUGUGACUUGAUCAUUUUCAAGGGGGCGCUGAUCUUGAUUCAUUUGAUCUUUGUUCAUGGCUACUUCAAAAAUAAAGACAUUCCCAUUUGUGUCAAGAUACCGUGGAUGCCUUUCUGUGUGACUGAACAAAAUAUUUUCUCUUUGUUCUUCAUUCUUAACAUUACAUGAAAAAUGGAAGGACAAUUUGAGUCCUAAGAAAGAAAACCAAUAGCAGCAAGCAUGGGAGACAAGUACCAAGAGGUGGAUAACAAGGGAAAAAAGAUGAAAUACACUCCUAAAAGGAAAAGGGGGAAAAAAAGUCAAGGCAGAACCCAGGAGCCCUGGCACCUAGUGGUGUCAGCCAAUGACACAGAUGAAAUGGGCAAUGGUAGUUGCACAUCCCGCUGGAAAAUACCACUGUCUCAGCCCAUUAGUACUGCUAUAACAAAAUACCACAGACUAAGUAAUUUAUAAACAACAGAAAUUUAUUUCUGACAGUUCUAGAGGCUGGGAUAUCCAAGAUCAAGGUGCCAACAGGUUUAAGGCCUGGUGAGGGCUCUGUCUCUGCUUCCAAGAUGGCACCUUGUUGCUAAGUCCUCCAGAGGGACAAAUGCUAUGUCCACACAUGACAGAAGGGUAGAGGGCAAAAAGGGCUUAGCUAUCUCCUUCCAGCCCUUGUACAAGGUCAUGAAUCCCAUUCACGAGAGCCCUGCCAUUGUGACCUAAUGACCUCCUAAAUGCUCCACCUCUUAAUAUUAUCACAUUGGAUCUUAGGUUCCAACGUAUGAAUUUGUGGGGAAACACGUAUAUUCAAACCAUGGCAACUACUUUAUAGUUUCAAAGCCUAAAACAUUGCAAAGCACUAUCUUGAUAAACACCUCAUUUGAUUCUAACCACAACAAAAUGAGGUAAGUGCAAUGGGACAGGGAUCACAUACCCAGUGAGUCAACUGUGUUUUGGAACGUUUAAAUGACUCCACAGGGCUCCCUUGGCUGUUAAGUGUUCCAGGCAGUGGCCAAGCCUUGAUUUUCUAUUUCUAGAUCUAGUGUUCUUUCUGAGGCACAUGUUAAGAUAUGCUGUAUAUGCUGUAUACCCUUUCAUCUAAUCUUGACCUGGAUUUCCAAGGUAAAAUUUUCUCCAUAUUCUAUCUCAUUUCCUGGCCACUAUACUCCUCCUUCUCCAUCCAAAAGUCACUCAAUGGUUUCUUUCAGUCAGAAAAUAACACCGAAUGGAAAAUGAGAAUGGAAAGGAGAAGAGAAGCAUGUAAAUGGGGCUGUGACGACAAAAUUUCAUCUUAGGAUACAAUUGCUUUCAUCCUGGACAAAAUGCUUUCAGAGAGAUUACCACAUUGUAUGACCAAGCAAGGGUUACUAUUACGAUUUUCAUUCUGCAGCUGUGAAAAUCAAGACUCAGAAACAUUAAGGGCCAUGUCCAGUGAUAGGUAUCUUAAAAGAUCGAGAGUCAGAUCUCCAGCCCUUGCAUCUGCCUCCACCUCCCUACAGUGGACACAGCACUGGCUUGACAGUCGGCUCUUAGGUUCCUGUCCUUCCACUAACUAGCUGUGUGAUGCUGGUCAAGUCUUGUAAGCCCUGGGCAUCGUUUCUUUCUACUGUCAACCGAAGGGGCUGGGCUGCUUGGUCUCUAAGAACAUCCUGUAAAGUAGCUGAUAAGAAAGAAAUUGCAACUGCUGGUCUUUGAAGACCAGUCAGAGGUGCCCUGAUCUCUCCCAGCACAACAAUGAGAAGGUGUUCAGCUAAUAUCACACUUUUAGAAAAAAUAUUGUCCAGACUCACUGUGCUAUUUCCCAAAUAUGAUUUGGGGAGCGAGCCAACAGAUAAAGAAGGAUAUUUAUUUUUGUUUGUAAUGUCGACGUCUUCUUUCGGGCUCGAUCAAACAAUCAGGAGAUCUGUGUAGGCCACAGCGUCAUUGCACGCCGGGGUCCUUGCCCGCUCCCUCUCUCUGCCACCGCUCAAAGCCUGGGAGAACGCUUUUGAAAGCGAAUCAGGAAAUUACUUAUCAAUCUGAAGCCCCAAAGAAUUAUGAAUAAUCCUCGCUGCCAAAGGGAAGGGGAUUUUGAGCAAAAGCUCCACAUCUGCGCACACUAGAGUUCAAAGACUCCAGCUGUUGGAAGGUCUUGUGAGCAAUAGCCAAAGAUGUUUGUCUUGCUCUAUGUUACAAGUUUUGCCAUUUGUGCCAGUGGACAACCCCGGGGUAAUCAGUUGAAAGGAGAGAACUACUCCCCCAGGUAUAUCUGCAGCAUUCCUGGCUUGCCUGGACCUCCAGGGCCCCCUGGAGCAAAUGGUUCCCCUGGGCCCCAUGGUCGCAUCGGCCUUCCAGGAAGAGAUGGUAGAGACGGCAGGAAAGGAGAGAAAGGUGAAAAGGGAACUGCAGGUUUGAGAGGUAAGACUGGACCGCUAGGUCUUGCCGGUGAGAAAGGGGACCAAGGAGAGACUGGGAAGAAAGGACCCAUAGGACCAGAGGGAGAGAAAGGAGAAGUAGGUCCAAUUGGUCCUCCUGGACCAAAGGGAGACAGAGGAGAACAAGGGGACCCGGGGCUGCCUGGAGUUUGCAGAUGUGGAAGCAUCGUGCUCAAAUCCGCCUUUUCUGUUGGCAUCACAACCAGCUACCCAGAAGAAAGACUACCUAUUAUAUUUAACAAGGUCCUCUUCAACGAGGGAGAGCACUACAACCCUGCCACAGGGAAGUUCAUCUGUGCUUUCCCAGGGAUCUAUUACUUUUCUUAUGAUAUCACAUUGGCUAAUAAGCAUCUGGCAAUCGGACUGGUACACAAUGGGCAAUACCGGAUAAAGACCUUCGACGCCAACACAGGAAACCAUGAUGUGGCUUCGGGGUCCACAGUCAUCUAUCUGCAGCCAGAAGAUGAAGUCUGGCUGGAGAUUUUCUUCACAGACCAGAAUGGCCUCUUCUCAGACCCAGGUUGGGCAGACAGCUUAUUCUCCGGGUUUCUCUUAUACGUUGACACAGAUUACCUAGAUUCCAUAUCAGAAGAUGAUGAAUUGUGAUCAGGACCAAGAUCCCUGUGGUAAACACUCUGAUUGAAUCUGGGGUUCCAGAAGGUGGAACAAGCAGGAAUGGGAUCCAAAGAGACUCCCACUCAGAUUCUAAAGCAUUUAAAGACAAUUCUAGCAGAAUUUAUCAAAACAAGAUGAAACACAGAAAAGUUGAAACCACAACAAAAUGAAUUCUAUUAAAGAAUAGCCCCAGAUAUAAAUUCUCUUGAAAGCAAUGUUCAUAAAUAUUUAAGCAAAUUAAAGACAAUGUUAACAAAUUUUCUAUUAAAUGCCCUGAGUGAUAAAACCAGUUGGCAAUAAUAUUGCCUUAUUAAAUCUUCAAAAAAUAUAUUUUAGUCUGUUAUUUAAGAAAAACAUAACAUCCCAAAAUCUUUGACAAUUCUCGAAAGGCUAUAUAGUAAGUCAAAAACCAAAGGUAAGAGAUGCUAACUAUUUUUCAAGCAAGCUACAGAGAAAUGAUAAAUGUUUUUUGUUUUAUUAUUUAUUCCUUCAUGUUUGUAUAUAUUCACUCAACAACCCUUUAAUGAGCCUGUAAGGACCAGACACUGUGGCGCUGAAUCAGAUUUAAUAAUGAGUUAAGACAAAGCCCCUACCUAUGGGCUAGUGUGUGGUGAUCAAACUAUCACAAUUCAGUGUGAUGAGCAGCAUAGCAAACAGAUGGAUUUGAAGCUAAAAGCACACAGGGUCUGCUAUUCCUGAGGCUGGGGGCCAGAGAAGCUUUUACGCAUGGAAAAACACUAAUCAUGCCAAGGUGUAUGUGUUUAAGGGGGUGUGAUGGAUGCAAAGGGAAUGAGGAAUUCAGCACUGCAUUCUCUUUGCACCCUCAAUGCAUGAUUGGUAUUCUCAACAGCAAAGGGGUGAAAAAUCUAGAGACAGAGGAGGCCUGGCAGGGGUGAUAAAAAUGGAGAUUGAAAUGAAGAGAAAUAGCCAGCAGGUGAUUCUUCUGAAUCCUUUAGUGUGAUGGUUUCCCAAGACAAACAUUUGUCCUAAUAGCUUUCUCAUAAAUAUGGGCACCACUUUACAUUGUGGUAAGACAUUGCUUCUCAUGGAUCUGCUAGGUAUUUAUUUCAAAUAAAGCAAGGCAUAUGUUCACUGAUUUACGAGUAAGCUGAUGAGAGCAAUGAACAGGAGAAGGAGGGAGAGAGCCAAAUGUCUGAGUAAACAGAUAUCCCUUCCAAGUCUCACACCUCCCUUAGUCCCACUCUUGCUUGUGUCAGCACCUUGUUCUUCACUGAACUGCAAUUCUUCAAUUAUUCUCUUCCAUGAUUUUGUCUGAUCUACCAUUUCUAUGGUUUAUGGUAAUAGUAUUCCCUUUAUCCCUCCCUUUUGGUAACUUCCAAUCCUCCUUCUAUGUAUUCCUUUCUCUGCUCAUUGACUUAUAAAUAGUUUUCAUACCUCUUAUGUUUGAAUCACCAUGCUAGAUUCUGUGAAGACAGAAGAGUAUCAAGAUUAAUAUAUUAAUAGUAUAGCUCUGACUGGUAAAUUUCUUUUUUUUAAUCUUCCCCAAUUUAAAUUUUUUAAUUUAAAAGUAAAUUUUACUGUCGAAAAUGCAAACUUGGGGAGGGCGGAAACAUCACACACAAGGUUUCCACUUCACACUUGGAGGGUUGCAUGGCGGCUGGGCAAAGGUGCUCCCCACUUCCCAGAUGGUGCGGCGGCUGGCCAGAGGCACUCUUCACUUCCCAGACAGAGGGGCGGCCGGGCAGAGGUGCUCCUCACUUCCCAGAGGGUGCAGGAGCCAGCUCUGACUAGUAAAUUUCUAAGGAUACCAGAAAGGAAAUGGCAUGCACACACACAAAAAAUACCUAAAUUUUGGAUGAGAAAAUGAUAAAAUAUGCUAAGUUCUAGGCUGGAAAUAAGGGCAAAAUGCUGUGAAAGAAGAGGAAAUGUUUACUUCCAAAUUAGGAUGUGACAGAGAAGGGAUAGGGAAAUCCUCUCUGCUCAUUGGGCCUUACAUGAUGGGUGACACUUGGAGUGGCACAAGUUGGGGGAAAGCGCACUUGAGACAGAGGUAAUGAUGGGGACGAAGUGAGAACAGAGACCCAGAAGGAGAAUCAAUGGACCAUAUUUGUAAGAGCUUUGAAAGCCAGCCUGAGAAUUGGAGGAUUUAUUCAUAAGAAAGUGUAGAGACCCUGUGUAUUUCAGAGCUGGAUACUGCCAUUACCACAGAUGAAAGUUGCAAUGAUCUAGCAGUUGUGUGCAAAGGCAAGGCUUGCUUUUCCUGUCUUUCAACCCUAUCUUGCUUUUCCUGUCUUUCAACCCUAUCUUGCUUUCAUUGUCUUCAUCUUCCUGCCAUACUUUGUGCACUUAUUGCUCUCCUUCUGAGUCAGGACAUGUGUACAGGAGACCAAGAACAAUGAGUAUUAGAAAAAAAGGAGACAGCAAAGGUGGUUUGAGGUAGUCACCUGCUUACAGAUAACAGCCAAAGAUAGAAUUCCAAGUUAUAAAGCAUAAAAAAGAGCCAACAGAAGUAACUAAUCCGGGAAAAGUGAACAUAUGGGCCCUUUAAAGACUACAAGAUUUGCUAGAUAAACUGGAAAUGGAGAAGUUAUUGCAGACAGUCAUGAACCACAAAUCACUGUGAUUAAAAUUUUCUUCUGAUCGUAAUCCACGAAUGCAUUCAUUUUUUGGACAUUGCUUACUUAUCUUUUAAAUGUUUCUUUUAUUACAAAGCCUAUUUUGAGUAGCUUUUAAAACUGAAUUUCCUUUAAUUGGUUUGAAGCCUAGAGAUGAAUUUCGUUUUCAAAUAUCUGGUGGGAUGGUAAUGGGGAUUAGAGAACUGACAUGAGAAAAGAGGAGCUGUUUUGGUAUUAAACGAAUAAAAUCUUAAGCAAAUAUAGGUGUCUUUUAUUCUUAAAAAAUAGCAGAUACAGUUUAUCCACAUUUGUAAAUAUUUGUAUAAAGAAAGUAGCAAAACAGUUUUGGUUUAAAAAGUUCCAAGUCUCAUUGCAAUCAUUCUUUGUAAAGGCUGACUUGUAAUGAAUAUGUAUUAAGCAAUAUUUAUUGACUAUACACCAUCUUGUUCUAGAAGAGUUUAAAGCCACUUAAGAAGAUAAAUAAGAUAUAAAAAGAAAACAGCAGUCAAAAGCAGAUGAGAAGAAAUGGGAAAAACAAAAAAAAAAGAAAAUAAUGAGGCUAAUAUAAUGCUGUGUGUACAUGAACAUGAAUGUGCCUGUGUUACACAUUUUCAGGCCACAAAUGUUUCUUUGUGCCCCUGCAUGCACAAGGGUAUUUCCAGGUCAUUUAUCAUUGUGAACAGUGUUGCUUAUGAUAAAAAAUAGAUUCUAUAAACUCUAAAUAUACUUUUUUUCUACCACUCUGUGUAAAAGAUCAUGAACGUAAAUAAAUUUUAGAUAUGA